GCUCGAGAGCGUCAUCGCCCCCGACUGUGGAGAAGUGUCCGGGGUAGCCCCGUUACAGGUAUCGCUGGCUACCCUCCUCCUUCGCCCCUCCUUUCCUCCUUUACAUUCAAAUCAAGUCGGGGUUGAAUUUCGAGAGGGGAGUCCGAGGACCUGGGGCCUGAUUUCUUUUUCUCUCGCCAUGCUUCUUCGGGCUGUGUACAUGUGUGGUGGUGCCUGAGAGGCGAUACAGGGAAUGGCUACACUCUUUUACUCCCGCCCCUGGCCUUCGUAGUACCCUUGAAGUGAUCCACUAGUCGUAACCCCUCCUUCCACCAAUGAUUCAAUUGGAGAAGUUUAGAGGAGUGGAAAGACUUGUCCCCUUCCCCCAUCGCAAGCUUGGUCACAGAGUGUAUUGCCAACCCAUGUAUCCAGACGCUCAGUCUAGGGCUCUUGGCCCUGGGUAGCGUUUUGAAAAGGCUGGUUAUCCUUAAGUACUGAAGAUUGAUAAAGCCCACUUACUUACUUAAAAGAAUAUGCCCUGAAAUGUGUUUUCUGUGCCACUGACACCAGAAAUGCUAUUUAGAAGAAGUUAUCAGUAAUCCUGACAAAGGAUGCUUCCUGCAGCUCAAAUCAGGCUGGAGGUGCCUUUAUAUUUUUCAUUGAAUUACUGUUUUGGUGACUCGAAUGAAUCAUCAAUUCAUUUAUUUGUCUUCAAAUGUCUGACGGCACUUAAGGUCUAAAAAAGAAGGAAUGUGUUUCUGAUCAUCUGAAUCUUAAUCAUGUCCAACUGCCUGCAAAAUUUCCUGAAAAUUACAAGCACUCGUCUUCUAUGUUCAAGAUUAUGCCAACAGUUAAGAAGUAAAAGGAAGUUUUUCGGAACUGUGCCAAUAUCCAGAUUGCAUAGGCGAGUUGUCAUUACAGGCAUUGGCUUAGUGACUCCUCUUGGUGUUGGAACUCACCUGGUUUGGGAUCGUCUUAUCGGAGGAGAGAGUGGAAUUGUUUCACUGGUUGGUGAAGAGUAUAAGAGUAUCCCUUGCAGUGUUGCUGCUUAUGUGCCAAGAGGUAGUGAUGAAGGUCAGUUCAAUGAACAAAACUUUGUGUCCAAAUCAGAUAUCAAGUCCAUGUCUUCUCCCACCAUCAUGGCCAUUGGGGCUGCAGAAUUAGCCAUGAAGGAUUCUGGCUGGCAUCCUCAGUCAGAAGCUGAUCAAGUGGCUACUGGUGUUGCAAUUGGCAUGGGAAUGAUUCCUCUUGAAGUUGUUUCUGAAACUGCUUUGAAUUUUCAGACAAAAGGUUACAAUAAAGUUAGCCCAUUUUUUGUCCCUAAGAUUCUGGUCAAUAUGGCAGCAGGCCAGGUCAGCAUUCGAUAUAAACUCAAGGGCCCAAAUCAUGCAGUAUCCACAGCCUGUACCACAGGAGCUCAUGCUGUGGGAGACUCAUUUAGAUUUAUAGCCCAUGGUGAUGCUGAUGUGAUGGUGGCUGGAGGUACAGAUUCUUGUAUUAGCCCUUUAUCUCUUGCUGGGUUUUCCAGAGCCCGGGCUCUGAGCACAAACUCAGAUCCCAAGUUGGCAUGUCGACCAUUUCAUCCAAAGAGAGAUGGUUUUGUAAUGGGAGAAGGUGCAGCUGUGCUGGUGCUGGAAGAAUAUGAACAUGCUGUUCAAAGAAGAGCCCGGAUCUAUGCAGAAGUUUUGGGCUAUGGACUCUCAGGUGAUGCUGGUCACAUAACUGCCCCUGAUCCUGAAGGAGAAGGUGCCUUAAGGUGUAUGGCUGCUGCUUUAAAAGAUGCAGGUGUGCAGCCUGAGGAGAUAUCCUAUAUCAAUGCACAUGCUACUUCCACACCAUUGGGAGAUGCUGCUGAAAACAAAGCUAUCAAACAUCUCUUCAAAGACCAUGCAUAUGCCCUUGCAGUUUCCUCAACUAAGGGAGCAACAGGACAUCUGCUGGGAGCUGCAGGGGCAGUCGAGGCAGCUUUUACCACAUUAGCUUGUUAUUAUCAAAAACUACCACCUACUUUAAACCUGGAUUGUUCGGAACCAGAAUUUGAUCUCAACUAUGUUCCACUAAAGGCACAGGAAUGGAAAACUGAGAAAAGAUUUAUUGGCCUCACCAAUUCCUUUGGUUUUGGUGGUACUAAUGCAACACUUUGUAUUGCUGGACUGUAGAACAUAUAAUUUGUAAUUAAAUACUGAUUUUUAAAUG